ACUUCCUGAAUCCGAAAGCCACAGGGAAAGAGCCUAUAUAUUUGUAUUAAAGAGCACCCUUCGCUUGACUUCAGGUCUUAUUCUGCUUCCAGUUAAAAUGAAGGUGAAAUAAAGACAUGUUCCUGCUGCUCUUUUUACUUCUGUUUGAGGGUGAGCUGAGGGAGUUGAAGGCUCAUUCUGGCACACUUGUGAACUGCAGGUGGAGGGGCUUGGUGUGAAGGAGUGUUUAAAGAUAGAGAUGGGGAGGAGGCAGCAGCAGGGAGUCAAGGAAGGCAGGAGUAGCCCUCUCCGUGUGUGGAAAAAGUGACUGGCAGCCAGGUGAGGAGUGGAUGGGAGAGGGGGAGGUGCAGGCCAAAGAUGGAGGGACCAGCUGGGAGACGGCUGUAAUAGUUCUGUGGCUCUGUGAGUGAGGAUGAAAAAUGCCUUUUACCUGUAAUUAGAGAAGCUUGGUUUCAUCUUUAACAUAUUGGAACUGUGAAAUUAUUAUUUUAAAGGACAAAGAAUUAUUUUCCUAUUACCAAUCACUUUCCUAAGUUACUGUGUGUUUGGUUUUUUUAAAGCAGGGCACAGUUUCAGGGAGAAAGAUCGAUACUCUCAUUUGAGACUGAGCCAGAUACUUUCCUUUCUUGUCUAAAGGAAGGAGGGAAACGAACACCUCCUUCCCUCUCCUGUUGACUUCCUGGCAAAGAAAAAAUAGACAAUUCGUUUUCCUGGGUGGGGUCAGGAGGAUCUUCAUCAUGAACAGACUGCAGCCAGCAGCAGGAGUGCUCUUCUCAGCCCCUGUGUAUGAGACCCCGUGCUAGAUGGUGGAAUAGUAAACAAGGAACCUGUCCUUGAUGAAAUCACCGCGGGGGUUGAGGGGACACAGCACUAGCAGAUAAGUAAUUAUGGCGAAGAGUGAGCUACCAGAACAACCGAAAAGUGCAGAGGAAACAGUUCUUUCUGGAGACAUUCUGGAAAGCUCAGCAGGGAUUAUGUGUGAGCUGCGUUUUGAAGGACAUGCCAGAGUCCCUCCCGGGGAAGGAGGGGACAGGCCUCCUGGGUACCCUGAUGAGAAGGCAUACUGUCCAGAUGAUGCCACAGGAGUCAGCAGAUCUCAGAGAUCCUAAUUGCUCAUGACCCCAAAAGAUAAUCCCUCAGGAUAGUCUCCCAAAUGACCGGCUGAACUCCAGGAGCAGGAAAAUUCAGAUUCGAAACAUCCCUCCUCACCUGCAGUGGGAGGUGUUGGAUGGACUUUUGGCUCAAUAUGGGACAGUGGAGAAUGUGGAACAAGCCUAAAGAAGUAAUUCAGAAGAACACACAAUCCAGUGAUGUUUGCAACAAAGUCAACACAGACACAGAAACCGCCGUUGUCAACGUCACAUAUGCAACAAGAGAAGAAGCAAAAAUAGCCAUGGAGAAGCUAAGCGGGCAUCAGUUUGAGAACUACUCCUUCAAGAUUUCCUACAUCCCGGAUGAAGAGGUGAGCUCCCCUUCGCCCCCUCAGCGAGCCCAGCGUGGGGACCACUCUUCCCGGGAGCAAGGCCACGCCCCUGGGGGCACUUCUCAGGCCAGACAGAUUGAUUUCCCGCUGCGGAUCCUGGUCCCCACCCAGUUUGUUGGUGCCAUCAUCGGAAAGGAGGGCUUGACCAUAAAGAACAUCACUAAGCAGACCCAGUCCCGGGUAGAUAUCCAUAGAAAAGAGAACUCUGGAGCUGCAGAGAAGCCUGUCACCAUCCAUGCCACCCCAGAGGGGACUUCUGAAGCAUGCCGCAUGAUUCUUGAAAUCAUGCAGAAAGAGGCAGAUGAGACCAAACUAGCCGAAGAGAUUCCUCUGAAAAUCUUGGCACACAAUGGCUUGGUUGGAAGACUGAUUGGAAAAGAAGGCAGAAAUUUGAAGAAAAUUGAACAUGAAACAGGGACCAAGAUAACAAUCUCAUCUUUGCAGGAUUUGAGCAUAUACAACCCGGAAAGAACCAUCACUGUGAAGGGCACAGUUGAGGCCUGUGCCAGUGCUGAGAUAGAGAUUAUGAAGAAGCUGCGUGAGGCCUUUGAAAAUGAUAUGCUGGCUGUUAACCAACAAGCCAAUCUGAUCCCAGGGUUGAACCUCAGCGCACUUGGCAUCUUUUCAACAGGACUGUCCGUGCUAUCUCCACCAGCAGGGCCCCGCGGAGCUCCCCCCGCUGCCCCCUACCACCCCUUCACUACCCACUCCGGAUACUUCUCCAGCCUGUACCCCCAUCACCAGUUUGGCCCGUUCCCGCAUCAUCACUCUUAUCCAGAGCAGGAGAUUGUGAAUCUCUUCAUCCCAACCCAGGCUGUGGGCGCCAUCAUCGGGAAGAAGGGGGCACACAUCAAACAGCUGGCGAGAUUCGCCGGAGCCUCUAUCAAGAUUGCCCCUGCGGAAGGCCCAGACGUCAGCGAAAGGAUGGUCAUCAUCACCGGGCCACCGGAAGCCCAGUUCAAGGCCCAGGGACGGAUCUUUGGGAAACUGAAAGAGGAAAACUUCUUUAACCCCAAAGAAGAAGUGAAGCUGGAAGCGCAUAUCAGAGUGCCCUCUUCCACAGCUGGCCGGGUGAUUGGCAAAGGUGGCAAGACCGUGAACGAACUGCAGAACUUAACCAGUGCAGAAGUCAUCGUGCCUCGUGACCAAACGCCAGAUGAAAAUGAGGAAGUGAUCGUCAGAAUUAUCGGGCACUUCUUUGCUAGCCAGACUGCACAGCGCAAGAUCAGGGAAAUUGUACAACAGGUGAAGCAGCAGGAGCAGAAAUACCCUCAGGGAGUCGCCUCACAGCGCAGCAAGUGAGGCUCCCACAGGCACCAGCAAAACAACGGAUGAAUGUAGCCCUUCCAACACCUGACAGAAUGAGACCAAACGCAGCCAGCCAGAUCGGGAGCAAACCAAAGACCAUCUGAGGAAUGAGAAGUCUGCGGAGGCGGCCAGGGACUCUGCCGAGGCCCUGAGAACCCCAGGGGCCGAGGAGGGGCGGGGAAGGUCAGCCAGGUUUGCCAGAACCACCGAGCCCCGCCUCCCGCCCCCCAGGGCUUCUGCAGGCUUCAGCCAUCCACUUCACCAUCCACUCGGAUCUCUCCUGAACUCCCACGACGCUAUCCCUUUUAGUUGAACUAACAUAGGUGAACGUGUUCAAAGCCAAGCAAAAUGCACACCCUUUUUCUGUGGCAAAUCGUCUCUGUACAUGUGUGUACAUAUUAGAAAGGGAAGAUGUUAAGAUAUGUGGCCUGUGGGUUACACAGGGUGCCUGCAGCGGUAAUAUAUUUUAGAAAUAAUAUAUCAAAUAACUCAACUAACUCCAAUUUUUAAUCAAUUAUUAAUUUUUUUUUCUUUUUAAAGAGAAAGCAGGCUUUUCUAGACUUUAAAGAAUAAAGUCUUUGGGAGGUCUCACGGUGUAGAGAGGAGCUUUGAGGCCACCCGCACAAAAUUCACCCAGAGGGAAAUCUCGUCGGAAGGACACUCACGGCAGUUCUGGAUCACCUGUGUAUGUCAACAGAAGGGAUACCGUCUCCUUGAAGAGGAAACUCUGUCACUCCUCAUGCCUGUCUAGCUCAUACACCCAUUUCUCUUUGCUUCACAGGUUUUAAACUGGUUUUUUGCAUACUGCUAUAUAAUUCUCUGUCUCUCUCUGUUUAUCUCUCCCCUCCCUCCCCUCCCCUUCUUCUCCAUCUCCAUUCUUUUGAAUUUCCUCAUCCCUCCAUCUCAAUCCCGUAUCUACGCACCCCCCCCCCCCCAGGCAAAGCAGUGCUCUGAGUAUCACAUCACACAAAAGGAACAAAAGCGAAACACACAAACCAGCCUCAACUUACACUUGGUUACUCAAAAGAACAAGAGUCAAUGGUACUUGUCCUAGCGUUUUGGAAGAGGAAAACAGGAACCCACCAAACCAACCAAUCAACCAAACAAAGAAAAAAUUCCACAAUGAAAGAAUGUAUUUUGUCUUUUUGCAUUUUGGUGUAUAAGCCAUCAAUAUUCAGCAAAAUGAUUCCUUUCUUUAAAAAAAAAAAAUGUGGAGGAAAGUAGAAAUUUACCAAGGUUGUUGGCCCAGGGCGUUAAAUUCACAGAUUUUUUUAACGAGAAAAACACACAGAAGAAGCUACCUCAGGUGUUUUUACCUCAGCACCUUGCUCUUGUGUUUCCCUUAGAGAUUUUGUAAAGCUGAUAGUUGGAGCAUUUUUUUAUUUUUUUAAUAAAAAUGAGUUGGAAAAAAAAUAAGAUAUCAACUGCCAGCCUGGAGAAGGUGACAGUCCAAGUGUGCAACAGCUGUUCUGAAUUGUCUUCCGCUAGCCAAGAACCUAUAUGGCCUUCUUUUGGACAAACCUUGAAAAUGUUUAUUUAAAAAAAAAAAAGAUGACAAAGAAAAACAGAGAGAGAGAAUAUUGGAGAUGUCCUGAAUUUUAAUAGGGUACGCGCCAUUAGGGCUUUUUGCGCUAAAGGAUGAACAUGUACUGGUUUAUGUGGACAAGCCAUUAUACCACCAGACUGCAAUGCCAGUUUCCUCUACUGCAAACAGUGUUCUGUGACAAAAAAAAAAAAAAAAAAAAGAAAAAAAAAGAAAAAACAGAAAUAUAUCCAGCUAACAAGAUCCUGGUGUCUUGGUGUUUUAUUUUACUAGGCAUUGCCUCAUCCCAGGUGUCAGCUGAGUCCUAGCUCUGAGGGACCUGGGCAGACAGGCGGUAGGUGUGACCUGGAUCCACACAGCUACUCUGAGAAAGCUGGUUUUGCCCAGGAAAGUCUUUGGGAGAAGCUAAACUAGAUCGGUGGUCAAAGUGUAGUCCCCAGACCAGCAGCAUCAGCUAUCAUCUGGGAACUUGUUAGAAAUGUAGAUUCUUGGGGUCCACCUUGAAUCAGAAAUCCUGGGGGUGAGGCCCAGCAACCUUUUCAGCAAGGCCUCUGGGUGAUUGCUGUGCGCACUGAAGUUUCCGAACCUCGGAGCUAGAGGGAUGGAUCGACUGCAUGUCAAGCUAGAGAAGACCAGUCUAUCCUUAAGGAACUGCAAGCCUGGCCAGGCAAAGCUGCUUUUUAAGUGGAGGAAAGGGGGAGGAUAAUAUGCCCGGCAGUUCCGGGAAGAGGCACUUCACGCCUCCACGGGAAGCUCACUAGUAAGUGCAGGCAUACCUCAGGAACGUCGCAGGUUCAGUUCCAGACCACCACAGUAAAGCGAACUUUGCAAUAAAAUGAGUCAUACACGUUU